GCAUACAGCCCGCAUCCCGCCGGGGAAGCGAGCCCAGUCCAGCGCUGCCCGUCCAGUCCUCGCCCAAGAUUUAAAGCCCGCAAGUUUUGUUCUUGAGACCAGCGACUUUAGCUCCGAUGCGGGAAGGAAAGCCGACCUCCGAUUUGGACAUUUAAAGAGCUGGGCUUGAACUUCGUGAGUUUCGCUCUAAACUGCCCUUGAAAUGAAGCUGGACUUGGAGGUCCAGAUUCCAGCUUGCACUGGAAUAUUUAUUGACCCUUUGAUAGAAGAGCUACACCUGAAACAUCUCUGAAGUCUUUUUAGCAUCCUAUCCUGCCCAUGGCCUACUACACAUUGGUUGAAUCUGAGGAUGCGGAACCCAUGAACGUACACGACCAACUGCAUAUGGGUUUCUAAUAACAGAUUUGUGGAUGAAGCCCACCCAACAUAAUGCAACAUUUCAAAUGUAUCUUAGUCAGUUUUUCUGGGGCAAAGCCAGCCUAACAAAUCUCAAGAAUGUUUGAAAAAUUCUAGCUUGAGUGAACGUUGUUCUUCUAGUGACUCAAAUAAAGCAGUCAUUGUGUCUGAGGAGUCCUAGUGGGGUGGCAGGGGUGGGGCUAGGAGUAGUGGCUGUUUGUAGCAUGUUUUAUAUCACAUUAAAGGGCUGGGUAUGCAUUUUAGGCAAUAAUUCUUACUCUUAUUGAUAGGAGAACUUGUAUUUUUUAUUCAUCUACCUUAUGAUGGAUAACUGGUUUACAUCUCUUCAUCAGGUUUACUUCUUACGUGUCAUUUUAUGAGCUGACUUUGAAUAUAUCUUCAGAUUUUCCCUGCCUUUACACAUGAAAACGGUUUUGAUACAGCUUUUUCAUUAGAGAAUGGCAGCUUUUCCAGGCCAGGGUGUCUGUGUCUGACUCCUCGCCUUUCAUUUUACCCAAUACUUGCUUAAAACAUCCUCCCUGAGUCCGGUACUUUUUUGCCUCCUCUCCUUCCUUCCACCCCACCUCUUUUUGUCACCCUCCUGCGACUUUGGAUCUCCAUCCUUGGAGUCCCUGAAUCUUUUUUGUGGUUGAAAGACUACACCCAAAGGACACAGACUGAUGAGGUCACUUCUGCCCACUGUCUAGUACUAGUGAGACCAAGAAGAAGAAGGAGGGAAAACUGAAAUGGAAGGUUUGAAAAAGAGUGUGUUAGUGAAGGAAGUAAGAACAGUGCUAACAGAAUGCAGCAAAACAGAAAUGACUUCACACUUCUGGCAGUGAAGCAAAUUCUCAUCCAUCUUGGGUUGCUUCUCUUGACCCUGCCCACCUCCUCCCCUGCCCUCCCCUCCCGAUGAGAACUGCAGGAACACCUGUGCCCAUGCCAAGGAAAAAGGGCAGGUGAGGAACACAGGGAUGGGGCUGGGACUCACAAGCUGCUCUAAGCUGCCACAGGGUCUGGAAUUUGUUGACAUUACAUGGUUAACUCGGUAUCUCGAUGCCUCAGUAUCUUCUGCAAAAUGUGGAGGGAGAUCCUUUCUUCCUCAAAGGUUGUUGUAAGGCUUAAAGAGCUACCACAUUCGUAAGGCAUUUGGAACAGGGCCUGGUAUAUAGUAGACAUACCCAUGGUAGUAACUGUUGCUAGACUGGGUAAAAGGAGAAGUUUCUUAAGUAGGCAAGAAAAAAACUGACAACAGUUAUAUUUAAAAGAGCAAGCAACCGUGUCAGCCCAAACAAGUGUGUUGCAAGAAUGAGCACAGAGGGCCAAGCUCAGAAAAGCGAGUGUUUGACCUCUCUGAGACCUCCUUUAUAUGUCAGCUUUUUUAUUUGUUUCAAAUUUUGCAUAAUCAAACUGGUUACUGGGAAUUAUUGAGUUCAUAUAACUUCCCUAAAAUCUAAGAAUAAUCUAUAAUCCCAUGCCACCAGUCCCGUUAAUAAAGACUUAGGGUCUGUCUUUACCCAUUUGUUCAUUUGAAAUUCCCCGUCUUUACUUCCCCCAUAACCAGGAAACAGAUCUACACCCAUGUUUAACUUAUAAAGAGAUAUAAGUGAGUUUACAUAGGUGGAGAUCUUGUACCUGGAUUCACAUUGUAGGUUUUAUUACCCAGCUUUCCCCUCUAUCCCAAAGCCAUGAUUGCCAUAGUGGAAUUUAAAGUCUUUGGACUAACACUGAAUCAAGAACUAACUCUACAAAUGUAUUCUCUGCAGGAGGAUAAGAAUUCCAAAUGGCUUCUAAUUGUUGCCCAUGGCUUGAAAUAAAGUUCCAUAUAGCUAAAGCCCCAGCACAAAAACACUUGAAGACAGCCAUUAGGUAGAAUUUCUUUUCUUUUUUAGAGGUCUUAUAUUGGAAAUGUAACAGUUGCAAAGAUAUCUAAUGUUUCACCUUAAAAUGUGAGUUAUAAAUUCACAUUUCACAUUGCCUCCUUCCUCCUUGAGCAAACAGACUAGGCAAUUAGUACCAAAUAGUAACUAGUUAUAUUUCUUAACACCGAUUAUUGUAAGUAAUUUAUUAAGAAAAAAUCUAGGAAGAUCAAAUUAUAGCUUUUCCAGUAAAUCUGGGGCUUUUUAUUCCUGAUCUCUCUCAACAAGGCAGUUUGGCUUCUGAAGAUUGGUCCUAGCUAUACUUAACAGGAAACAGAUGACGAGAAGAAGCCAGGAAAAAAUACUUGGAAUAUAGAACAAAAUGCAGCAUAAAGAUGGUACAGAAGAUUUUAUCUUUCUUUCCUUUAGUUAUGUGUGGACAGGAACUAAAAACUCUCCCACGUGGGACUUUAUUAAGUAAUAAAAGUUUAAAUGUAAAAGAUAUAAAGGAAUGAGGAUAUAAAGGAAAUUUUUUUAAAAACUGUGACUCACCGGAGGAGCCUUAUAUAGUCUACUUUCUAAGCAUAUCACUUUUAAAGGGAUCAUUAUAUUUUCAUGAUGCAUGGGGAUAUUCCAAGUAUUAAAUUGAUUUUUUAAAUGAAGAAAAUUAUCAGUUCAGUCUUGUUUUCUAUGUAGGUUUCACUACAGUAUUUUAUUUCCCCCGCAAGGAAAAAACCAGAGCUAGAAUGGAAUGAUUAAAUUUCUUAGUUUUCUUCUAAUCUGUUAGUCUUUCCAUUAAAUUAUACUGCCUUCUUAUAUAGAAUUUCUGGGUUUGUUCUUGUUUUGGCAAUAAUUGAAGUAAGAGAGGAUGAUUUUAUGGUAGAGGUUUGAUUCCAUUCUAGAUUGGUGUUUUUCAGCUAUGUAGAACACAAUCCAUUCAUGGUUCAGACAACCGUUUUAGGAGGUUUUCAUGUCCAGCAUUAAAAAAAAAAAAAAAAGAAUAGAAUUGGGCAUUCAUAUAUAUAUAUAUAUAUGAAUAUUUAUUAAUAAAAGUUUAAAAGAUAUAAAGGAAUGAGGAAUGCAUAUAUAUUAUAUAUAUAUAUACCAAAUUAAAGUAUCAUAAUACUAAUACAAGGAUUAGUAUCGUUUUAUGAUACUUUAUUAUAUACACUAAGGGUUAGUCUUGUUUUAUGAUACUUUAUUAUAUACACUAAGGGUUAGUCUUGUUUUAUGAUACUUUAUUAUAUACACUAAGGGUUAGUCUUGUUUUAUGAUACUUUAGGUUGGUAUACAUACAUAUACUAAGAAUGCAGACAUGUCCAUGGAAGUUGGCAAUAUUCAGCCCCCAGCAGGCCCCAGUCAGCAGGACAGGGAUUAGGGGAGUCAGGUGAGGCAGGGCUGUAUAAGUGCAGGGUUGGAGCCUGUCUUGGUUUACCGUUUUGACAUUUUGUUCACUGUGGAUUUUUUUCAGUAACUUUGAUUUUUUAAAAAUAUUGCAUCAAAAUAUUAUACUGACUACGGAGUUUUUGGUACCCCCUUAAAUUGUGCACCUAAAAUAAGUGGCUCCCUUGUCUCCCCCUAGUCCCGGCCCGAUCAGUAUGUUUUAUAGAGGGAAUGGUGAGUGUUGGGGAACUAGGGAGCCCAUGAGGAGGCGGCCCAGAAGGGGAGGAGGAGCUGAUGGUGUGUCUGAUGUCUCCUCCUUUCUCUAGGAAGCAGACAGGAGGUGAAGUCUUCAGGGUGGGGGGGACAGAGCCUGGGAGGGGGAGAUUUAGCAUGGCCGCUGAAGAGACUGGGAAAGGGAGAAGGUUCGGGACAAGUUCAGGAACAGUCACGUAGCACUGAAAACUGCUCAAAGCUAGAUAGUGCCAUUUGUGGUGACGCUGCCUGCCUGGUAAGUCCCAUUUCCCCAGCAGCCCUGGAGGUGUCAUAGGAACAGGAAGAUGGGAGGGCGCUGGGGUCUGGGGUUGUUGGGGUGGGAGGGCAAAGGUGUCCAAUGAUUCUGCAUCUGAAACGGGGGAGGUGUGUGAGGAAGAAAGGUCAGGAGACUGCUGGGCAGGGUGGGGUGGCAGAAGGUUCUCGAUGAAUAUUUAGAAGUUGCAGCUGAGGAGUGAGUGUACUAUAGAGUGAGUAUCCUGGAAUUUGAGGUCUCAGAAGAAAUGCAGUUCUCAGUGAAGCCAUGUAAACAACUUCCUGGCUGAUAAGGUGUCUUGAGUGUUGGGAGAUCACAUGAUCAAAAUGGUAUACACACCAUAAGGUGUCCUUAGACUUGAGUGUGGUGUAAGUCUACUGAAUAAAAUGCAGAAAUACAGUUCACUGUUGCUUUUCUUCCUGGAAAUUGCCCUCCCCAACCUCAAACCAGCCCCCAAGUGGGGCAGGGUCCAUCUUUAGACCCUCCUGUAGCACCCAGCACAACCCUAACUAUAUGGUCAAUGUCUCUCUUCCCCACUUAGAGCUCCAAGACCAGGGCCUUGUUUGUCCUGCUUACCCACUCUACCCAUUUGUUAACCCCAUCUUAAUUUUCUGAUGAAUGAGCCCUUUUUUCAUUGACUCCUCCUUUCUCUCCUUCUCCGGAGUUUAUUUUUCCUCCAGGCCCAUUGCUGUCUCUCCACCUAGAGAGCUUAUCCACAUUCAUGAAAUUAGUCAUCUUCAUGCUCAGAGUACCCACCUGGAUCUCUCCAGUCCUGUCUAACUCGUCUUAGAUUAUUACCCCCUGGACAUCUGUACCUUCUUGUCUCUCCAUCGCCUCGAACUCAAUGCGAGUCUAAAAUCAAAUACUCCUUCACUCCUAACUCAGGAAACCAGUUUUCCCUCCCUUGUUGGUAAUGCUUGAAAUUAGCUCUUACUUCUCUUCUUCCUCCUUUACUCGCCAUCCCAGGUCAUUCAUCAGGUCCUGCUAGGUCUUUGAUUUUCUUGAAAGGGCCUUCUUUAUGCCUUCCUUCCGUCCCCAUUUCCACCACCCUCGACUAGGCCUUCCUCACCUCAUCCGGCAUCAGUGUGAGCCCUUGAGAAACCAGCGUCCUGAUCUUCAGGCAUUCUGCAUUUCACCCCAUACCACCAUUAGCCAGUUUAAUCCCUCUUGCUCAAACUUAAUAAAUACUGAGCAAGGGAGUUACUAUAACAAACAAAACCAGAAAUUUCUAUGACUUCCUGCUGCUUUCUGUACCCCCCUAAGACUCCUCUACCUGAUUUUCAAGGUUCUCCAUAAGCAGGUUCCCACCUCUCUGCUUUCAAAUCUUCUAUCUGCCAUACACAGUUCUUGUCUAAAACAAAGAUUGUUCCUACUCCUGCAGCCACCUAAAUCCUAGUCGUCCUCAGGCCCUCCUAAAAUCCUGACUAAUCCAACCCCCACCGAUUUCUCUACUAGUCCCAGAGACUUCCCUCUUGUGCCUGGGGUUGGUGUCAUGCAGACACACUGUACCUUACCAGGAUUUGCCCAUUGUUGUCUGUGGGAACUAUGCUUUCAUGUGGGAACUACGAGUCUUGUCACAAAUAGAGUGUAAAUGCUUUGAGAUUGGAGACUGUAAAAUACUUCUUCAUGAUCUCCCACUGUGUCUGGUAUAAGAACCCGCAGAGUAAAUACUCAUAUACUUGUAGGAUUAAUUGAAACAACUGGAGACUGAGGUUGUUUAACUUGUACUUAGAAGUGUGGACCUCCCCAUCUUGAUUAAAACUUCAAAACGGAUAGCAGGUUUCACAUAUUAUCUCAGCAUCACAAAAGUAGACUCAACAAAGAAAUGAGUUGACAGCAGGGGUAAGGUUUACAACAAUCAGGGAUUAUUGCAGGGAAACUUGUAGCCUUUGGGUGUUCUAACUAGUUUUUUCCCAAAAAGUUUAAAGAGCUCUCUUGUGAAAGAAUAUUCUUAUGAGUAACUGAGGGGCACGGCUCCUAGACUGAAAAGUAUUUGGGAUCUGUCACCUCUUUUCUGAUGUUCCUACUUCUAUUCUUUAUUCUUCUGACUACCUCUAUUAGAAAAGAUAAUACUAAGAAUACCUGUCCCUUCUUCUCAGUCCAAAUAGAAGCAAACCCAGGUUGUAUCUGAGAUAUCUGCAUAUUUUCUUCUAAGCAAUUCUUUGUCCUCUUCUCUCCCAUGCUUUUUCUAUUUCCUAUUUUCAGCAGGCUCUGAAGUCAUUUAUAAUUUUUACUGCCCCUCGGUGACAUUACAUGGAUAUUCAUCCCUGAUUUGCAGAUUAAAGCACCGAAUCAGAGUGAGGUGAGGGUUGCCCAAGGUUACACAAUAAAUCUGGCCCCAAACAGGGGUAACCCUUGAGUUUCUAGUCUGUUGAUUGGCCACUGACCCGUGCUGCAGGCACACAAAGGAAGCUGCACCCACAGCAGUCUGUUGUGGAUGGUUGCUGAGCUGCGCAUUCGGCAUUGGGCUUGCUUUGUUUCCUGCCAGGCCCAGCAUUUUCUUCUACCAGAUCGGCAGGCUUGUGGGCUUCUUCCUAGGUCCCUCCCCUGCACUCUGAAUAGGAAAGCUGGAAGCUGUGCUUUAGAGAAGCUUUAAGACGCCGAAAGAAACCAGAAGAGUGAGCGCCAGUUGUAUGUGCGUGGUCUCCAUCCGCAAAGCCGGAGCUGGGCGCAACAGUGUUGACUUAAAGCAUUUUGACUUGUUGAUGUCAAUUUGGAACAGCUGAAAAAAUACAGGAAAAUAAGAUAAAUACGUACAUGUUGAGGGUGGGGACAAAAUGAAGGUUCUGAACCAGCUGCCGGCUUACAGUAGCCAUAUAAGCAACAGCAGCAAUGCACCAACCUGGUGGCAUGGAAUAUUCACAUGGGAGAGCCGCAUGAGGCCGCCCACCACGCUUCCUGAAGGAUGCCCGUGUGGAAGAAUUUUGACGUGCCAGUGUCCUCGUUCUACAGGGUGUUCCAUUCUUCCGCAAUCUCAGAAAAAUGGGACUAAAAGAAACUAUUUUGUAAAAUAAGAAGACUUCCAUUUUUAAUGACCAACAUGUAUUAAGAUGGACACCUACUCUACGAAACACGAAGUUCUAUGGUCUCGAAGAAGCCCGUGCCUGUUUAAAACUGAUCCUAACUAAAAACAGACUUGAGUGGAUAUGAGAAUGUUGGUUAGUGGCAGAAGAGUCAAAAAAUGGCAGUUAAUUAUUCAGUUAUUUGCUACUUGUUUUUUAGCGAGCCUCAUGUUUUUUUGGGAACCAAUCGAUAAUCACAUUGUGAGCCAUAUGAAGUCAUAUUCUUACAGAUACCUCAUAAAUAGCUAUGACUUUGUGAAUGAUACCCUGUCUCUUAAGCACACCUCAGCGGGGCCUCGCUACCAAUACUUGAUUAACCACAAGGAAAAGUGUCAAGCUCAAGACGUCCUCCUUUUACUGUUUGUAAAAACUGCUCCUGAAAACUAUGAUCGACGUUCCGGAAUUAGAAGGACGUGGGGCAAUGAAAAUUAUGUUCGGUCUCAGCUGAAUGCCAACAUCAAAACUCUGUUUGCCUUAGGAACUCCUAAUCCACUGGAGGGAGAAGAACUACAAAGAAAACUGGCUUGGGAAGAUCAAAGGUACAAUGAUAUAAUUCAGCAAGACUUUGUUGAUUCUUUCUACAAUCUUACUCUGAAAUUACUUAUGCAGUUCAGUUGGGCAAAUACCUAUUGUCCACAUGCCAAAUUUCUUAUGACUGCUGAUGAUGACAUAUUUAUUCACAUGCCAAAUCUGAUUGAGUACCUUCAAAGUUUAGAACAAAUUGGUGUUCAAGACUUUUGGAUUGGUCGUGUUCAUCGUGGUGCCCCUCCCAUUAGAGAUAAAAGCAGCAAAUACUACGUGUCCUAUGAAAUGUACCAGUGGCCAGCUUACCCUGACUACACAGCCGGAGCUGCCUAUGUAAUCUCCGGUGAUGUAGCUGCCAAAGUCUAUGAGGCAUCACAGACACUAAAUUCAAGUCUUUACAUAGACGAUGUGUUCAUGGGCCUCUGUGCCAAUAAAAUAGGGAUAGUACCGCAGGACCAUGUGUUUUUUUCUGGAGAGGGUAAAACUCCUUAUCAUCCCUGCAUCUAUGAAAAAAUGAUGACAUCUCAUGGACACUUAGAAGAUCUCCAGGACCUUUGGAAGAAUGCUACAGAUCCUAAAGUAAAAACCAUUUCCAAAGGUUUUUUUGGUCAAAUAUACUGCAGAUUAAUGAAGAUAAUUCUCCUUUGUAAAAUUAGCUAUGUGGACACAUACCCUUGUAGGGCUGCGUUUAUCUAAUAGUACUUGAAUGUUGUAUGUUUUCACUGUCACUGAGUCAAACCUGGAUGAAAAAAACCUUUAAAUGUUCGUCUAUACCCUAAGUAAAAUGAGGACGAAAGACAAAUAUUUUGAAAGCCUAGUCCAUCAGAAUGUUUCUUUGAUUCUAGAAGCUGUUUAAUAUCACUUAUCUACUUCAUUGCCUAAGUUCAUUUCAAAGAAUUUGUAUUUAGAAAAGGUUUAUAUUAUUAGUGAAAACAAAACUAAAGGGAAGUUCAAGUUCUCAUGUAAUGCCACAUAUAUACUUGAGGUGUAGAGAUGUUAUUAAGAAGUUUUGAUGUUAGAAUAAUUGCUUUUGGAAAAUACCAAAUGAACGUACAGUACAACAUUUCAAGGAAAUGAAUAUAUUGUUAGACCAGGUAAGCAAGUUUAUUUUUGUUAAAGAGCACUUGGUGGAGGUAGUAGGGGCAGGGAAAGGUCAGCAUAGGAGAGAAAGUUCAUGAAUCUGGUAAAACAGUCUCUUGUUCUUAAGAGGAGAUGUAGAAAAAUGUGUACAAUGUUAUUAUAAACAGACAAAUCACGUCUUACCACAUCCAUGUAGCUACUGGUGUUAGAGUCAUUAAAAUACCUUUUUUUGCAUCUUUUUUCAAAGUUUAAUGUGAACUUUUAGAAAAGUGAUUAAUGUUGCCCUAAUACUUUAUAUGUUUUUAAUGGAUUUUUUUUUAAGUAUUAGAAAAUGACACAUAACACGGGCAGCUGGUUGCUCAUAGGGUCCUUCUCUAGGGAGAAACCAUUGUUAAUUCAAAUAAGCUGAUUUUAAUGACGUUUUCAACUGGUUUUUAAAUAUUCAAUAUUGGUCUGUGUUUAAGUUUGUUAUUUGAAUGUAAUUUACAUAGAGGAAUAUAAUAAUGGAGAGACUUCAAAUGGAAAGACAGAACAUUACAAGCCUAAUGUCUCCAUAAUUUUAUAAAAUGAAAUCUUAGUGUCUAAAUCCUUGUACUGAUUACUAAAAUUAACCCACUCCUCCCCAACAAGGUCUUAUAAACCACAGCACUUUGUUCCAAGUUCAGAGUUUUAAAUUGAGAGCAUUAAACAUCAAAGUUAUAAUAUCUAAAACAAUUUAUUUUUCAUCAAUAACUGUCAGAGGUGAUCUUUAUUUUCUAAAUAUUUCAAACUUGAAAACAGAGUAAAAAAGUGAUAGAAAAGUUGCCAGUUUGGGGUUAAAGCAUUUUUAAAGCUGCAUGUUCCUUGUAAUCAAAGAGAUGUGUCUGAGAUCUAAUAGAGUAAGUUACAUUUAUUUUACAAAGCAGGAUAAAAAUGUGGCUAUAAUACACACUACCUCCCUUCACUACAGAAAGAACUAGGUGGUGUCUACUGCUAGGGAGAUUAUAUGAAGGCCAAAAUAAUGACUUCAGCAAGAGUGACUGAACUCACUCUAAGGCCUUUGACUGCAGAGGCACCUGUUAGGGAAAAUCAGAUGUCUCAUAUAAUAAGGUGAUGUCGGAAACACGCAAAACAAAACGAAAAAAGAUUUCUCAGUAUACACAACUGAAUGAUGAUACUUACAAUUUUUAGCAGGUAGCUUUUUAAUGUUUACAGAAAUUUUAAUUUUUUUCUAUUUUGAAAUUUGAGGCUUGUUUACAUUGCUUAGAUAAUUUAGAAUUUUUAACUAAUGUCAAAACUACAGUGUCAAACAUUCUAGGUUGUAGUUACUUUCAGAGUAGAUACAGGGUUUUAGAUCAUUACAGUUUAAGUUUUCUGACCAAUUAAAAAAACAUAGAGAACAAAAGCAUAUUUGACCAAGCAACAAGCUUAUAAUUAAUUUUUAUUAGUUGAUUGAUUAAUGAUGUAUUGCCUUUUGCCCAUAUAUACCCUGUGUAUCUAUACUUGGAAGUGUUUAAGGUUGCCAUUGGUUGAAAACAUAAGUGUCUCUGGCCAUCAAAGUGAUCUUGUUUACAGCAGUGCUUUUGUGAAACAAUUAUUUAUUUGCUGAAAGAGCUCUUCUGAACUGUGUCCUUUUAAUUUUUGCUUAGAAUAGAAUGGAACAAGUUUAAAUUUCAAGGAAAUAUGAAGGCACUUCCUUUUUUUCUAAGAAGGAAGUUGCUAGAUGAUUCCUUCAUCACACUUACUUAAAGUACUGAGAAGAGUAUCUGUAAAUAAAAGGGUUCCAACCUUUUAAAAAAGAAGGAAAAAACUUUUUGGUGCUCCAGUGUAGGGCUAUCUUUUUAAAAAAUGUCAACAAAGGGAAAAUAAACUAUCAGCUUGGAUGGUCACUUGAAUAGAAGAUGGUUAUACACAGUGUUAUUGUUAAAAUUUUUUUACCUUUUGGUUGGUUUGCAUCUUUUUUCCAUAUUGUUAAUUUUAUACCAAAAUGUUAAAUAUUUGUAUUACUUGAAUUUUGCUCUUGUAUGGCAAAAUAAUUAGUGAGUUUAAAAAAAAUCUAUAGUUUCCAAUAAACAACUGAAAAAUUA